GGAAGUGCGUGGCCGCCCGGGGCCAUGGCGACACUCAGCUUCGUCUUCCUGCUGCUGGGGGCAGUGUCCUGGCCUCCGGCUUCUGCCUCCGGCCAGGAGUUCUGGCCCGGACAAUCGGCGGCCGAUAUUCUGUCGGGGGCGGCUUCCCGCAGACGGUAUCUUCUGUAUGACGUCAACCCCCCGGAAGGCUUCAACCUGCGCAGGGAUGUCUAUAUCCGAAUCGCCUCUCUCCUGAAGACUCUGCUGAAGACGGAGGAGUGGGUGCUUGUCCUGCCUCCAUGGGGCCGCCUCUAUCACUGGCAGAGUCCUGACAUCCACCAGGUCCGGAUUCCCUGGUCUGAGUUUUUUGAUCUUCCAAGUCUCAAUAAAAACAUCCCCGUCAUCGAGUAUGAGCAGUUCAUCGCAGAAUCUGGUGGGCCCUUUAUUGACCAGGUUUACGUCCUGCAAAGUUACGCAGAGGGGUGGAAAGAAGGGACCUGGGAAGAGAAGGUGGACGAGCGGCCGUGUAUUGAUCAGCUCCUGUACUCCCAGGACAAGCACGAGUACUACAGAGGAUGGUUUUGGGGUUAUGAGGAGACCAGGGGUCUAAACGUCUCCUGUCUGUCCGUCCAGGGCUCAGCCUCCAUCGUGGCGCCCCUGCUGCUGAGAAACACAUCAGCCCGGUCCGUGAUGUUAGACAGAGCCGAGAACCUACUUCACGACCACUAUGGAGGGAAAGAAUACUGGGAUACCCGUCGCAGCAUGGUGUUUGCCAGGCACCUGCGGGAGGUGGGAGACGAGUUCAGGAGCAGACAUCUCAACUCCACGGACGACGCAGACAGGAUCCCCUUCCAGGAGGACUGGAUGAAGAUGAAGGUCAAGCUGGGCUCCGCGCUAGGGGGCCCCUACCUGGGAGUCCACCUGAGAAGAAAAGAUUUCAUCUGGGGUCACAGACAGGAUGUACCCAGUCUGGAAGGGGCCGUGAGGAAGAUCCGCAGCCUCAUGAAGACCCACCGGCUGGACAAGGUGUUUGUGGCCACAGAUGCCGUCAGAAAGGAAUAUGAAGAGCUAAAAAAGCUGUUACCCGAGAUGGUGAGGUUUGAACCCACGUGGGAGGAGCUGGAGCUCUACAAGGACGGAGGCGUUGCGAUUAUUGACCAGUGGAUCUGCGCACACGCCAGGUGCCUGCCCACGUCACUGUCGGCCGAGAGCGGGUCGGGUGGCUUUCAAAGGUUCUUCUGUCCCAAGUACUCGGUGUCAGAGCAGAUGGUCGCCUGUGUUCACAGUGGUCAUUUCCAUACUGUUUGCCUCCUCGUCUGAGUCUCCUGUAGCAUCUGGUUCAGUGUUUCCCUGGGCUGAAGUUAAUUGUUCAUCUUGCCCCUUUAGUUCUCAUGCACAGAAUUCCUCCAUAGCAGGCUGUUGGCAUAGCUGGCCUCGUCUCAGAACCUCUUCUUGUGUCGCAUUUUCCCAUCAUUCCCGGUUUCUGCCCCUGUCUGCCCCCUGCCCUGAGAGUUGCCCGUGCCCUGGACUUGGGCAUGUCCUUGUUGCUGUGUUGUUGAGCAUCCGUGAGCGUCCCCGAGGCCGGGAGCGUGGGCCCUCGUGUGAUCAUUCUCGUGGGGCUGCCAUGAGCGUCCCCAAGGCUGGGAGCAUGGGCCCUCGUGUGAUCGUUCUUGUGGGGCUGCCGUGAGCGUCCCCGAGGCCGGGAGCGUGGGCCCUCGUGUGAUCAUUCUCGUGGGGCUGCCGUGAGCGUCCCAGAGGCCGGGAGCGUGGGCCCUGCGUGCAGUCAUUCCUCUGGGGUUGCUGUGGGAGGUACGCCUGGGCCUCUGUUCCUCCAAAGACCUGCCUGCCCAUCUGCAUAGGAGAUGAAGGCUGGGGUUAGGGUGAAACGGUUUGAGUUAAAUGGAAAAUGAAAGUAGAGGGAAUGAUCUUCCCCGUGGUUAGCACUGUGCACACGCGUGCGUCUCUGUGGGUUAGUCUGUCUCUCUCCUGCCCGAGGAAUGCUGAGCGCCCUGAGCCGGUGCCUCUUCACACAUCUGCUAUUUCCUGUGGUGUUCUGGGCAUGGUGUGUAAGACCCACAGAGGCUCCGGGUGAUGCUGUCUGCUGGGUGUGGGUCCCUUUCCCUGUUAAGCAGACAGGAUGCAGCGCUGACUUCUUAGGUCAGGGCGGAGGUGUGCAGGAGCCCAGUUACGAACUCACCCCUGCUUCUCAGGUGUGGCCUUGGGAUUUUGACUGCGACCUUGGCGGUGCUGUCUCCGCAGCCCAGGAAGCCUGCUGUGGGGAGGCUUCGCACUGAGCUCUCAGCCUCCUGCCCUCAGCUGCGCGAAGCGCUCGGCCCAGCUCACUGAAGCUGCCCUGCCUCCGGGCCGGCGCGGCCUGCUCUGGCAGGCCCCUGUGUGUGGGGUGGUGAGGGUCUCCCCACCAGUGCUGCACCCCGCAGCAGCAUACAGGCCUGUGUGGCCUGCUGGCCCUGUGGCUCUGUGUACAGCGCUGUGCAUGUUACAUUUGCUCUGGAAACAUCUCUGGGGUUUGCUUGUUCACGAAGUUCAUGAAGUGCCGCUGGAGAGCCAGAGACCAGCUGCGCAGGAGCCGGAGGAACGGGCAGGCCGCUGACCUGAGGUCUGGAGAAACCCCUGGAGAAGGGUGUCCCCACCAGCCCAUACAGCGUGUGUGUGGAGGGGGCCUUGACCUCCGUGAUGUCUACUGUGCCUCAGGAUAAGGACCCGCCAUGCCCUGGCUAGACAGUGUGUGGUUAGUAGGAAUCUCUCAUUGUUCACCAUGUGACCCCCAGGAGGUAUUCGACCUGCACUGGCGUGCCUGGCCUGGGAUUUGGUGACGGAGAGGAGGGCUCCCAGGGGGACAUGCGGUGGGACAGGAGCGUGGCGGCUGCUGACUGUGGGGUGUGGAUGGGGCUGCAGCACCAGGCAGAGCCCCUCAGGGCGCCGAUGUCGAGGGCACCUGAGCGAGGGGUGCCAGCAAGGGGGCGGCCGGCUGGUGGGUGCUCGGGGGACGGCCGUGUUGGUUCCAUGUAACUGUGGAACUCAUUUCACUCAGCUGCUCCUCUCAGUUCUCCCUGACUCUGGAACCUCUGUGACGCCAGUUCUCCCUGACUCUGGAACCUCUGUGAUCCUUUGCAGGUUUUUUAUUGGCACCUCAGUCUCAACAUUUUCUUUUCGGAUUCAUGAGGAAAGAGAAAUCCUGGGGUUGGACCCCAAGACGACGUACAACAGGUUCUGCGGAGACCAAGAGAAGGCGUGUGAGCAACCCACCCACUGGAAGAUCACCUACUGAGGAGGAUCCUCCAGGGCCGCUCCCCGGACCCGACAGGCGCGGGUGGAUGCAGGUUCUGUCGCCGUGGAGUCACCGUCUACUGCCAGCCGGGAGCUGGGCGGACAGGACCGUCCCUCGCAGGGUCCCAGGCCCAGAAGAGGCCCCACGCCUCUAGAGCUGGGCUCCGUCCUCGGCGUUGCCAGCCGCCAUGGCUGAUGAAGAGGCUCCGCUGCUCUCGGGGGUGGCGGUUGUUUUCAGGCAGCGUCUGUGAACCCACAGCUCGGUUGCCAGCAGUGCCCGCGUGGUGACCCAGAAGCAGGAGUGUUUGUCAGGCUCCCGCUCUGGCCUUUCCAGCCACCUUUCAUGUCUUCAUAUUUUAAGUGCAUUGAGGAUAGAUGCAGGCGGGUGAGCUGCCCUCCGUCAGGUGGACCCGGGCUGACAUUUCCCUGGGAGCUGGUGCAAGGAGAAGCGUCAUUUUAAAUGUCUGCAGAGCGACCAGGGGCCUCAUGAAUCUCUCCGUUGCCCUCCGCGCAGCAGGAGGCUGCCUGUGUGUUUCCUCCUGGGAUGCGUGCAAGGCAGACCUGGUGCUGCAAAGGAAAGGGCCUGAGGCCUCAGGGAGCCCCGUGGAGGGAUGACAGUUCAGGCCCUACUGCUGGCACGUCAGAGCACUGGGAAGUUUUUCAGUGACGUCUCUGGGGCACUCAGUGGAUUGUCUGUAGGAAACUUGCAGCUCUGCUCCUCACACCAGGCCCGGCUGGCCACCCACCCUCGCCCCCACUGGCCACCCCUCCCUCGCCCCGACUGCCCCGCCCCACCCUCACCCCGACUGCCCCGCCCUCGCCCGGCUGGCCGUCCCUGCCCUCGCCCCGGCUGGCAGGUGCACAUGGGGCCUCCAGGUCUGCCAUUCGCUAUUGAGAACUAGAAAUGAGGAAGGACAGUUACGCUAACUCCAAAAGGCUGUCUAGGAUGAGCUGCUUUAUCAGGGAGCUCCUUGUACCCAUUUUACAGAAAUCAUUUUUAGGUCUUUGUGCCACCACCACGAGGGGCAUCUGCAAAGAGGGCAACGCUAGACACAGAAUCCGUGGAAGGUGCAGCAGUGCCUCAGGGGUCCUCAGGGUCAGGGAGCCCCCCUCACCCUCUUGGCCCGUUACCCUUUGUGACUUUCCACCAUGGUGUCGUGUGACCCUCAGUCAGGUUGGUGGGGGCUGAGUCCUCACUGAGCAGCCACUUUCCACAUCUGCUAGAGGAACAGUGACAUGGACACCUGUGACAGAGAGAGGACAGUUAGGAGGGACAGACAGCUCUUCCUUUCGGAGCCUGGCUAGUCUAGGACAUCACCUUGCUGUGUCUUCUCAAGCUUUUAAAAUUGACCCUGAACGUGUGACAGGGUCCUAUGGUGUUACUCAAAGCUGUGCAGGGUAAAUGAUGACAUAUUUAUUCUUUUUCCAUUUGUUCUAGAAACAGUGCCUUUUUCAUCAGUUGCAUUUUCCAGGCUGAGAGCUGUAUAAAACAUUUUGGACUGUGACCAUGUACCUUCCUUUUUAAGAAAAAUAAACUGCUUUAUGGAA